AUUUGUGGAGACCAGCCCUCUGGCUUGGUGAGUGAAUCUGGUUUACACCGGCUCCUGCCCUGCCUUCACUCUUCUCCCCUGAUUCAAGACUCCUCUGCUUUGGACUGAAGCACUGCAGGAGUUUGUGACCAAGAACUUCAAGAGUCAAGACAGAAGGAAGCCAAGGGAGCAGUGCAAUGGAUUUCUCAGUAAAGGUAGACAUAGAGAAGGAGGUGACCUGCCCCAUCUGCCUGGAGCUCCUGACAGAACCUCUGAGCCUAGAUUGUGGCCACAGCUUCUGCCAAGCCUGCAUCACUGCAAAGAUCAAGGAGUCAGUGAUCAUCUCAAGAGGGGAAAGCAGCUGUCCUGUGUGUCAGACCAGAUUCCAGCCUGGGAACCUCCGACCUAAUCGGCAUCUGGCCAACAUAGUUGAGAGAGUCAAAGAGGUCAAGAUGAGCCCACAGGAGGGGCAGAAGAGAGAUGUCUGUGAGCACCAUGGAAAAAAACUCCAGAUCUUCUGUAAGGAGGAUGGAAAAGUCAUUUGCUGGGUUUGUGAACUGUCUCAGGAACACCAAGGUCACCAAACAUUCCGCAUAAACGAGGUGGUCAAGGAAUGUCAGGAAAAGCUGCAGGUAGCCCUGCAGAGGCUGAUAAAGGAGGAUCAAGAGGCUGAGAAGCUGGAAGAUGACAUCAGACAAGAGAGAACCGCCUGGAAGAAUUAUAUCCAGAUCGAGAGACAGAAGAUUCUGAAAGGGUUCAAUGAAAUGAGAGUCAUCUUGGACAAUGAGGAGCAGAGAGAGCUGCAAAAGCUGGAGGAAGGUGAGGUGAAUGUGCUGGAUAACCUGGCAGCAGCUACAGACCAGCUGGUCCAGCAGAGGCAGGAUGCCAGCACGCUCAUCUCAGAUCUCCAGCGGAGGUUGAGGGGAUCGUCAGUAGAGAUGCUGCAGGAUGUGAUUGACGUCAUGAAAAGGAGUGAAAGCUGGACAUUGAAGAAGCCAAAAUCUGUUUCCAAGAAACUAAAGAGUGUAUUCCGAGUACCAGAUCUGAGUGGGAUGCUGCAAGUUCUUAAAGAGCUGACAGAUGUCCAGUACUACUGGGUGGACGUGAUGCUGAAUCCAGGCAGUGCCACUUCGAAUGUUGCUAUUUCUGUGGAUCAGAGACAAGUGAAAACUGUACGCACCUGCACAUUUAAGAAUUCAAAUCCAUGUGAUUUUUCUGCUUUUGGUGUCUUCGGCUGCCAAUAUUUCUCUUCGGGGAAAUAUUACUGGGAAGUAGAUGUGUCUGGAAAGAUUGCCUGGAUCCUGGGCGUACACAGUAAAAUAAGUAGUCUGAAUAAAAGGAAGAGCUCUGGGUUUGCUUUUGAUCCAAGUGUAAAUUAUUCAAAAGUUUACUCCAGAUAUAGACCUCAAUAUGGCUACUGGGUUAUAGGAUUACAGAAUACAUGUGAAUAUAAUGCUUUUGAGGACUCCUCCUCUUCUGAUCCCAAGGUUUUGACUCUCUUUAUGGCUGUGCCUCCCUGUCGUAUUGGGGUUUUCCUAGACUAUGAGGCAGGCAUUGUCUCAUUUUUCAAUGUCACAAACCACGGAGCACUCAUCUACAAGUUCUCUGGAUGUCGCUUUUCUCGACCUGCUUAUCCGUAUUUCAAUCCUUGGAACUGCCUAGUCCCCAUGACUGUGUGCCCACCGAGCUCCUGAGUGUUCUCAUUCCUUUACCCACUUCUGCAUAGUAGCCCUUGUGCUGAGACUCAGAUUCUGCACCUGAGUUCAUCUCUACUGAGACCAUCUCUUCCUUUCUUUCCCCUUCUUUUACUUAGAAUGUCUUUGUAUUCAUUUGCUAGGGCUUCCAUAGCAAAGCAUCAUAGAUUGCUGAUUUAAACUGUAAUUGUAUUGCCGUACUGUGGGCUGGAAAUCCCAAAUCUAGAUUCCAGCAGAGUUGGUUCUUUCUGAGGUCUGCAAGGAAGGGCUCUGUUCCAUGCCUCUCUCCUUGGCUUGUAGAAGGCAUCUUGUCCCUAUGACUCUUCACAUUGUCUUUAUGUACAUCUCUGUGCCCAAGUUUUCCCUUUUUAUUAAGACACCAGUCAUACUGGCUCAGGGCCCACCGCUAAUGCCUUAAUGAAAUCAUUUUAACAUUAUAUUCUCUACAAAGACCUUAUUUCCAAAUAAGAUAAUAUUUGGAGGUAUUGGGAAUAAAAACUCCAACAUAUAAAUUUGAGGAAGGCACGAUUUCACUCAUAACAAUCUUACCCUUUCUUGCAAGAGAUGCUUGUACAUUAUUUUCCUAAUACCUUGGUUUCACUAGUAGUAAACAUUAUUAUUUUUUUUAUAUUUGCAAAGGAAACAUAUCUAAUCCUUCCUAUAGAAAGAACAGUAUUGCUGUAAUUCCUUUUCUUUUCUUCCUCAUUUCCUCUGCCCCUUAAAAGAUUGAAGAAAGAGAAACUUGUCAACUCAUAUCCACGUUAUCUAGCAAAGUACAUAAGAAUCUAUCACUAAGUAAUGUAUCCUUCAGAAUGUGUUGGUUUACCAGUGACACCCCAUAUUCAUCACAAAAUUAAAGCAAGAAGUCCAUAGUAAUUUAUUUGCUAAUAGUGGAUUUUUAAUGCUCAGAGUUUCUGAGGUCAAAUUUUAUCUUUUCACUUACAAGCUCUAUGAUCUUAAAUAAUUUACUUAAUGUAUUUUGGUGUAUUUUCCUCAAAUUAAUAUUGGUGUUCAAGACUAUAUCUAAUUCCUCUGAUCACUUUGAGAAACAAACUUUUAUUAAAUGUAAGGCACUUUUCUAUGAAUUUUAAAUAUAAAAAUAAAUAUUGUUCUGAUUAUUACUGAAAAGAUGUCAGCCAUUUCAAUGUCUUGGGAAACAAUUUUUUGUUUUUGUUCUGUUUUCUUUUUGCUUCAAUAAAACAAUAGCUGGCUCUA